AGUGCAGUGGCGUGGUCACUGUUGACUGCAGCCUCAAAUUCCUGGGCUCAAGAAAUCCUCCCGUCUCAGCCUCCCAAGUAGAACCAAAGAUUGGAUCUUCUGAGAACAUCAGAGAAAGAAUGUCCUUGCCAUCCACAAUACAGCAAAACUUCAGGACCUUGAACUUUGGGUUCAUAAUCUCACAAGAGGGAAGUUUUUCGCCAGAAAAAGAUGGCAUCCUUGAUGUGAACAGCUUUUCCCAAGAUCACAGAUCAAGACUUCUAGUUUUUUUUUUUGAGACAGAGUCAUUUUUUUUUUUUUUUUUGAGACAUAGUCUCGGUCUUGUUGCUCAGGUUGGAGUGGAAUAGCGCGAUCUUGGCUCACUGCAACCUCCGCCUCCUGGGUUCAAGUAAUUCUCCUGACUCAGCCUCCAGAGUAGCUGGGAUUACAGGCGCCCACCACCAUGCCCGGCUAAUUUUUUUGUAUUUUUAGUGGAGACAGGGUUUCACCAUGUUGGCCAGGCUGGUCUCGAACUCCUGACCUCAGGUGAUCCGCCUACCUCGGCCUCCCAAAGCGCUGGGAUUACAGGCAUCAGUCACCGUGCCCGGCCUUGUGAUAGUGUCUUACUCUGGCACCCAGGCUGGAGUGCAGUGGUGCAAUCUUGGUUCACUGCAACCUUCGCCUCCCAGAUUCAAGCGAUUCUUGUACAUCAGCCUCCCGAGCCGCUGAGACUACAGGCACGUGCCACCAUGCCUGGUUAAUUUUGUGUGUGUGUGUGUGUGUAUGUUUGUGUGUGAUGGAGUUUUGCUCUUGUUGCCCAGGCUGGAGUGCAGUGGUGCGAUCUUCGCUCACUGCAACGUCUGCCUCCCGGGUUCAAGCGAUUCUCCUGCCUCGGGCUCCUGAGUAGUUGGGAUUAUAGGCGCUCAACACCAUACCCGGGGAAUUUUUUGUAUUUUUAGUAGAGACGGGGUUUCAUCAUGUUGGCCAGGUUGGUCUCCAACUCCUGACCUCAGGUGAUCCACCCGCCUCGGUGUCCCAAAGUGCUGGGAUUACAGGCGUGAGCCCUGUGCCCAGCCUCAGUGUCUCUCUCUCUCUCGACUAGAGAGACUGACCAGGGACAAUCAACUCUCUCCAGACUGACAGAGAGAGAGACAGAGAGAGCGAGAAAGAGACAGAGUCUGGCUCUCACCCAGGCUGGAGUGCAGUGGUGUGAUCUUGGCUCACUGCAACCUCUGCCUUCCGUGUUCAAGCGAUUCCUGUGCCUCAGCCUCCCAAGUAGCUGGGAUUAUAGGUCCACACCACCACGCCCGGCUAAUUUUUGUGUUUUUAGUAGAGACAGCCUCACCAUGUUGGCCAGGCUGGUUUUGAACUCCUGACCUCAGGUGAUCCGCCAGCCUCGGCCUUCCAAAGUGCUGGGAUUACAGGCGUGAGUCACCGCGCCCGGCCAAAUAAAAUAAAAUGUUAAAGCAAAUUCAGGACUACCCCUCCUCCAAGUCUUCUGUUCCCUUUGGGCGCCCAGGUGAGCGGGGGAGGGGCUGGGGGAGUAAUAACAUCAAAAGAGCGCCUUUUCCUCCCUUAUUCCGAGGAGACUUCCCUGGGCCUGACUCCCGGUCCUGUCCCCAGCGCCCCGCGGCCUCUGGAGCCCCUUCAGUGACCAAGAUACAGAGAUCAGGACGCCUUUGCGCCGCCCCAGGUGCCCGCCCCUAGCUGGCUCUGCUUGGGCCGCGAGGGAAGGUGAGGUCGGGGGCGGAGCCGGGGCGUGACAGCCGGGGUGUGUGUCCGCCGGGCUUGGUGCCUCCGGUGGCCCUGCAGCACCGUCCCACCUCUGCCACCCUCCGAUGGGGCCGCUACCUGUGUGCCUGCCAAUCAUGCUGCUCCUGCUACUGCCGUCGCUGCUGCUGCUGCUGCUUCUACCUGGCCCCGGGUCCGGCGAGGCCUCCAGGAUAUUACGUGUGCACCGGCGUGGGAUCCUGGAACUGGCAGGAACUGUGGGUUGUGUUGGUCCCCGAACCCCCAUCGCCUAUAUGAAAUAUGGUUGCUUUUGUGGCUUGGGAGGCCAUGGCCAGCCCCGCGAUGCCAUUGACUGGUGCUGCCAUGGCCACGACUGUUGUUACACUCGAGCUGAGGAGGCCGGCUGCAGCCCCAAGACAGAGCGCUACUCCUGGCAGUGCGUCAAUCAGAGCGUCCUGUGCGGUUGUGAGAAUUUUGCCCCAAUAACAAAAAGCAGGAGUGCAUGGUGAGGAUUUCUCUGUUACUGAGAGUGGUUGGGGUGAGAGAAAGUCUCCCGGAGACACCAAUGAAGCAGAGACCUGAGGAACAGAGGAGACAGCCACGUGGAGGUGAUGCAACAGCCAGUGCAAGGGCCCUGGGGUACGCACAAGUGUCUGGGUGGUCUGAGGAUCACAAGGAGUUCGGUGAGGCUGGAGCAGAGUCCCCCAGAGUGACAGAAGUAGGGGAUGAUGUCGGAGAGUGAUAGGGGCUAGAUUCCUAGGGCAUUGGAGGCUCUUCUCUGAGAGAGAUGGGGAGCCAAGGAGGGUUUUGAGCAGGGGAGGGACA